UAACUGUCGCCAAGGCUGAAGUGCAGUGGCACGAUCAUAACUCACUGCAGCCUUGACCUCCUGGGCUCAAGCGACCCUCCCACCUCAGCCUCCUGAGCACCUGGGACCACAGGAUGCACCACCCCGCUUGGCUACAUUUUUAAUGUGUAGACAUGGGGUCUGAAUACGUUAUUGAGAGUGGUGCGGAACUCCUCCUGGACCGAAAUGAUCCUUCCACUUUGGCCUCUCAGAGUGCUGGGAUUACUGGCGUGAGUCACUGCACCUAGUCCAAGCUUUCGUUUUUUUGUUGGGGGGAGACGGAGACUCGCUCCGUUGCCCAGGCUGGAGUGCAGUGGCACAAUCUCGAUGACGGCUCACUGCAAUCUCCACCUCCCAAGUUCAAGCAGUUCUCCUGCCUCAGCCUCCCAAAUAGCUGGGAUAACAGGCACACGCCACCACGCCUGGCUAAUUUUUUUUGUAUUUUUAGUAGAGACAGGGUUUCGCCAUGUUGGCCAGGCUGGUCUCGAACUCCUGACCUCAGGUGAUCCACCCACCUCGGCCUCCCAAAGUGCUGGGAUUACAGGCGUGAGACACCGCGCCCGGCCCCAAGCUUUCUUUAAACGGGGAAAAUAUGCACAUAAAAAUUCAAAAGGCCUAGGCUGGGCAAGUUGGCUCAUGCCUGUAAUCCCAGCACUUUGGGAGGCCGAGGCGGGCAGAUCACUUGAGGUCAGAUUUGAGACCAGCAUGGCCAACAUAGAGAAACAGUCUCUACGAAAAAAAUAAAAAAUUAGCUGGGCAUGGUGGCGCACGCCUGUGGUCCCAGGUACUCUGGAAGCUGAGGCGUGGGAGGCUGAGGCACGAGAAUUGCUUGGACCCAGGAGGCGGAGGUUGCAGUGAGCCGAGAUUGCGCCACUGUACUCCAGCCUGGGCGACAGAAUGAGACCCCCUCUCAAAAUAAAAAUAUACAUUUACUGUAAAAAUAUAUUUGUCCACCACGUGGAAUGAUCUGGAUUUGCUAACCCAUAAAGCUGACCGGGACUCAUUGUCCAUGGAGAGCGCACUCGCCUUCCUCGGGGAGAUGGUGCUUCGCCUCCUUCCUGCACUUCCAGCCCCACUGCCCCACCCGGCAGGCUCAUGCUGACUGUGCUUUGCUGACAAUCUGCUUAGGAGCUGCCUCAGUUUGCUGAGAAGUGAAAUGUUCUUGGGGGAACCCUCAGGGUUGUUGUCCCGGUUCCUGACACUAAGGCCUGCAUUUACCAUGGUGCUCAGCCCAACACACCAGACAGGCACCAUUCCCCCACCUCUGCCAACGAGGAGAGCCCCUGGGGGUUAACACUGCCGCUGGUGCCAGCACUGAUGGCAGCAUGGCAGUCAGGACCCAGGCCUGACAGAGUCCCCGGCAGCUACAGAAGUGCAUGCUCCCUCUCUGCACGGGCCACUUCUGGUACCUCUUGGUGUUGAAGUAAUUUAAGUCAGAACCCCUUUUAUUGCCCCAGGGGUGACCGGGAGGCCGUGGUCUCGGGGCUUUGUGUUUGCAGGAGUGUGGGGCUGGGGCUGCCUUUUCCGCGUCCCCUGGAGGAGACCUCAGGCAGCCUCUGUAGGUCUGAGGACCCGCCUGCAUGCCAGGUUCUCCGGGAGGCUUUGGACUUGGGAGCCUUUGAACGUGCCCUUGAGAGGCGGAUCAGAAGGGGGCAGGUUUUACGCAUCAUGUGUUGAGCCCCUCACAUGCACCCUCCAAGGACCUGUCGGGGAUGGAGCAGCUUGCUGGAGACAAGGGGCAUGGCCUCAGCGGUGGCGCCGGGAGCCUGGAAACCUGGCCGGCGUCAGGCACAUCAUCCUGGUCCUCUCAGGAAAGGGGGGCGUUGGGAAAAGCACCAUCUCCACGGAGCUGGCCCUGGCACUGCGCCAUGCAGGCAAGAAGCGCUGAUAAAGCAGUUUGUGUCCGACGUGGCCUGGGGGGAGCUGGACUACCUGGUGGUGGACACGCCCCCGGGGACCUCCGAUGAGCACAUGGCCACCAUAGAAGCCCUGCGUCCCUACCAGCCCCUGGGGGCCCUCGUGGUCACCACGCCCCAGGCGGUGUCCGUGGGGGACGUGAGGCGCGAGCUGACCUUCUGUAGGAAGACGGGCUUGCGGGUGAUGGGAAUCGUGGAGAAUAUGAGCGGCUUCACCUGCCCACACUGCACGGAGUGCACCAGCGUCUUCUCCAGGGGCGGCGGAGAGGAGCUGGCCCAGCUCGCCGGGGUGCCCUUCUUAGGCUCCGUGCCCCUGGACCCUGCGCUCAUGAGGACCCUGGAGGAGGGCCACGACUUCAUCCAGGAGUUCCCUGGGAGCCCCGCCUUCGCUGCACUCACCUCCAUAGCCCAGAAGAUUCUGGACGCGACGCCCGCGUGCCUCCCCUGACUAAGGCCACCUUGCAGCCGCUUUCCAGGGCCACCAAGGGCUCUGCUCCAGCCUCUCAGAGAAACAGAGGCCUGGGCUCGGUUCCCGGGCCCUGCAGGGGCAGGCCCAGGCAGCGUCAGCCGGAGAGCUUCUCCCCGACCAGCCCAGCCCCAGGAUGUGUCGCACCAGCAGCUCUGCCUGGUUGGCCUGCAGUGCCGUGGUCUGCGUGCUCUGCAGCUGUGAGACGGGGGCGGCCUGGGCUCUCUUCCCAUCCAUGUUGCCUACCUGUGCCCCUGGCAGCCGCGUGUCCACACAGUUAGCGGAGCGCGGGACUUCUGCAGUCCUCAGGUGACCCCGGGCCUCCAGCACCCUGGGUCGCUGUCAUCUGUGUUUAGCUCGGGGAGUGCCCCCUAAGGGGGCGAACUGACCUCAGGCAUGUUUUGUAACUGUAGAGGCGCCUGCCAUUAAACGUGUCCGCUGCUGUGGCGACAGA